GCCGUCGCCGUUGCCGCUUCGGGGCCUCGAGGGCAGCUCGGGGCUGCCCUCCUGUCACCGGCGCUUUUGCGUCCGGCCUGAGGGGCUGGGAGAGUGCGAGCGAGGCCGGGAGGGUUGGGUGAGGCGGUCGCCAGCGGCGGAGGUCGCGGGGCCGGCGGGGAGGCGGGGUGGCGGGGCGGGUUGCCGGCCGCCCGGGGAGGUCGCGGGGCAUUUUUCUUUCUCUCCUGCCGCAUAGUGGCGGGGGGCGGGUUGGGCGAGGGAGGGGCGCCCCGGCCGGGUCUUCGCUGUCAGGACCGCGCUGCCACCCUGCCGCCGGAGCCGAGGUCCCCAGGUUUUUCGGGCGAGGGCUUCUGCCUCUGCCCCGCUGGGUCCCCUCCUUCGCUCAUCUUUUCCCAGGCGCUGCGCGGCUUUUACUCUUUGCUGCUGAUCUGGGCGAGUUUAAUGGCGGAUCUGGGGCCCUGUCGUCGACUGCUGGGGCCCCAGGGCAACUUCUUGAGGCAACUGUGGGCCCAGAGGUGAUGCGCGCCGCCCGUUACCUCUGAAAUGGACCAGGAAUCACCUUCAAGCCUAUGUCGUGAGGCUUUGGCAGAAAUUAAGAAGGAAAUAUCUCCAUUGUUCAUUGGCAUGGAAAAAUGUUCAGUGGGAGGAUUAGAGUUGACUGAACAGACUCCUGCUUUAUUAGGGAAUAUGGCCAUGGCAACUAGUCUCAUGGACAUAGGGGAUUCAUUUGGUCAUCCAGCUUGUCCUUUAGUCAGUAGAUCUAGGAACUCACCAGUGGAAGAUGAUGAUGAUGAUGAUGAUGUUGUGUUUAUUGAAUCUAUACAACCUCCUUCAAUUUCUGCUCCAGCAAUAGCUGAUCAAAGAAACUUCAUAUUUGCAUCAUCAAAAAAUGAAAAGCCUCAAGGAAAUUAUUCUGUAAUUCCUCCUUCUUCAAGAGAUUUGGCAUCUCAGAAAGGAAAUAUAAGUGAGACAAUUGUUAUUGAUGAUGAAGAGGACAUAGAAACAAAUGGAGGAGCAGAGAAAAAGUCUUCCUGUUUUAUCGAAUGGGGACUUCCUGGAACUAAAAACAAAACCAACGAUUUGGAUUUCUCCACUUCCAGUCUUUCAAGAAGUAAGACCAAGACUGGAGUAAGACCUUUUAACCCUGGUAGAAUGAAUGUGGCAGGAGACUUAUUUCAGAAUGGAGAAUUUGCAACUCAUCAUAGUCCUGAUUCUUGGAUCUCCCAGUCAGCUUCAUUUCCCAGUAAUCAGAAACAGCCAGGGGUGGAUUCUUUAUCACCAGUGGCCUUACUUCGUAAGCAGAAUUUCCAGCCUACAGCCCAACAACAACUUACUAAACCAGCUAAAAUCACUUGUGCAAAUUGCAAAAAGCCUUUACAGAAGGGACAGACAGCUUAUCAACGAAAAGGAUCAGCUCACCUCUUUUGCUCUACCACCUGCCUUUCUUCCUUCUCUCAUAAACGUACUCAAAACACACGAAGCAUAAUAUGUAAAAAAGAUGCAUCUACAAAGAAGGCUAAUGUCAUUCUUCCAGUAGAAUCAAGCAAAUCCUUCCAAGAAUUUUAUAGUACAUCUUGUUUGUCUCCCUGUGAAAACAACUGGAAUCUUAAAAAAGGAGUUUUUAAUAAGUCAAGAUGUACAAUUUGUAGUAAAUUAGCAGAGAUUCGCCAUGAAGUCAGCGUAAAUAAUGUAACACAUAAACUGUGCAGUAACCAUUGCUUUAAUAAGUACAGAUUGGCCAAUGGUCUAAUAAUGAACUGCUGUGAACACUGUGGAGAGUACAUGCCUAGUAAGAGUACUGGAAACAACAUCCUGGUGAUUGGAGGUCAGCAGAAGAGAUUUUGCUGCCAAAGUUGUAUUAACGAAUAUAAACAGAUGAUGGAAACAAAAUCAAAAAAAUUAACAGCAUCAGAAAAUAGAAAAAGGAAUGCUUUUAGAGAAGAAAAUGAGAAACAAUUAUAUGGAUCGUCAAAUACACUUUUGAAAAAAAUAGAGGGAAUCCCAGAAAAAAAGGAAAAGACUUCACAGCUACAGCUUUCAGUAGAAUGUGGCACGGAUACAUUACUGAUCCAAGAGAAUGUGAAUUUACCUCCUUCUUCCACGUCAACCAUAGCUGAUACAUUUCAAGAGCAACUGGAAGAGAAAAAUUUUGAAGACUCCAUUGUACCAGUUGUGCUUUCCGCAGAUCCAGGUACGUGGCCCCGAAUUUUGAAUAUUAAACAACGGGACACUCUUGUUGAAAAUGUUCCGCCUCAAGUAAGAAAUUUUAACUUUCCAAAAGAUAAUACAGGGAGGAAGUUUUCAGAAACUUAUUAUACACGGAUUCUUCCAAAUGGUGAAAAAACCACUAGAUCCUGGUUACUUUAUUCAACCUCAAAAGAUUCUGUGUUUUGUCUAUAUUGCAAACUCUUUGGGGAAGGAAAAAAUCAACUGAAAAAUGAAAAUGGGUGCAAAGAUUGGCAACAUUUAUCACAUAUUCUUAGUAAACAUGAAGAAAGUGAAAUGCACGUCAACAAUAGUGUUAAGUACUCAAAAUUAAAAUCUGAUCUGAAAAAAAAUAAAGCUAUUGAUGCUGCAGAACACAGAUUAUAUGAAAAUGAGAAAAAUGAUGGUGUGCUGUUGUUGUACACGUAAUAUACCUGAGUUGUUUUUUGGCAUGAUGAUCAGAAUCUUACAUUACUCAGAAAACAUCUGUCCUGCAAUAGUCAGUACUAUUGUGUUGUAAGUCUCCUCUACAGAGUAACUUGCAGCAGUUCCUUAGCAAUAAGUAUGAUAGCAAAUAAAUAGCAAAGAAUGUUUCCAUUCUAAAUCUAAAACUAAUUAGAUUCAAUCAUCAUUAGGCAAUGACUUCAUUAGGCAAUGAAGAUUAACAAUAGGUAAUUGUUAAUCUUCAAAAUCUAUCAAUUUACACCUAUUUAAAAAUUGGCAUUUAAUGACUGCCAUUUGAUGGGUUUGGUUAAUAUUCUGUUCUUGGCCGGGCGCAAUGGCUCACGCCUGUAAUCCAAGAACUUUGGGAGGCUCAGGCGGGUAGAUCAAUUGAGGUCAGAAGUUCAAGACCAGCCUGGCCAACGUGGCAAAACCUCGUCUUUACUAAAAAUACAAAAAUUAGCCAGGUGUGGUGGCACACACCUGUAGUCCCAGCUACUCAGGAGGCUGAGGCAGGAGAAUCGCUUGAACCCAGGAGGCAGAGGUUGCAGUGAGCUGAGAUUGCACCACUGCAGUCCAGCCUGAGCAACAGAGCGAGAGUCAGUCUCAAAAGAAAGAAAAAUAUUAUGUUCUAAUUACCUUGAAAGAGGAAAGAAAGGCUUGAAUUGAUCAAUACCAGUUUGAAUAAGAUACUUAUGUGAACAAGCAUUCUCAACAUUAUUAUUAAAGUAAAACUACUCAGUUUACAGAAUGGGAUCUGAAACUACAGCUUUUUGCUAUUAAACCAAAUACUUGUGAUCUACUUUGUUUGAGCAAAACAGCAUUAUUUGUUAUGUUAAUGAUGGUUAAUUUCCAUUUUAUUGGUUUUAUGUUUAUUUUAAUUUGUAAAUGUUUUAGCAUUUAUUAUUGUAUGUGAACUAUAUUUACCUAUUUUAUGUUGAUAAAAAUAUAAAAAAUAUUAAAAUAAGUAUAUAUUAAGUUAA